AGUGGAGAGAGCGGGAGGAGCGAGGGAAGGCAGGAAGGAGGCAGCCGAAGGCCGAGCUGGGUGGCUGGACCGGGUGCUGGCUGCGCCGCGCUGCUUUCGGCUCCCACGGCCUCUCCCAUGCGCUGAGGGAGCCCGGCUGGGCCGGGCCGGCGGCGGGAGGGGAGGCUCCUCUCCAUGGUCCAGAAGACCAGCAUGUCCCGGGGCCCUUACCCACCCUCCCAGGAGAUCCCCAUGGAGGUCUUCGACCCCAGCCCGCAGGGCAAAUACAGCAAGAGGAAAGGGCGAUUCAAACGGUCAGAUGGGAGCACGUCCUCGGAUACCACAUCCAACAGCUUUGUCCGCCAGGGCUCAGCGGAGUCCUACACCAGCCGUCCAUCAGACUCUGAUGUAUCUCUGGAGGAGGACCGGGAAGCCUUAAGGAAGGAAGCAGAGCGCCAGGCAUUAGCGCAGCUCGAGAAGGCCAAGACCAAGCCAGUGGCAUUUGCUGUGCGGACAAAUGUUGGCUACAAUCCGUCUCCAGGGGAUGAGGUGCCUGUGCAGGGAGUGGCCAUCACCUUCGAGCCCAAAGACUUCCUGCACAUCAAGGAGAAAUACAAUAAUGACUGGUGGAUCGGGCGGCUGGUGAAGGAGGGCUGUGAGGUUGGCUUCAUUCCCAGCCCCGUCAAACUGGACAGCCUUCGCCUGCUGCAGGAACAGAAGCUGCGCCAGAACCGCCUCGGCUCCAGCAAAUCAGGCGAUAACUCCAGUUCCAGUCUGGGAGAUGUGGUGACUGGCACCCGCCGCCCCACACCCCCUGCCAGUGGUAAUGAAAUGACUAACUUAGCCUUUGAACUAGACCCCCUAGAGUUAGAGGAGGAAGAGGCUGAGCUUGGUGAGCAGAGUGGCUCUGCCAAGACUAGUGUUAGCAGUGUCACCACCCCGCCACCCCAUGGCAAACGCAUCCCCUUCUUUAAGAAGACAGAGCAUGUGCCCCCCUAUGACGUGGUGCCUUCCAUGAGGCCCAUCAUCCUGGUGGGACCGUCGCUCAAGGGCUACGAGGUUACAGACAUGAUGCAGAAAGCUUUAUUUGACUUCUUGAAGCAUCGGUUUGAUGGCAGGAUCUCCAUCACUCGUGUGACGGCAGAUAUUUCCCUGGCUAAGCGCUCAGUUCUCAACAACCCCAGCAAACACAUCAUCAUUGAGCGCUCCAACACACGCUCCAGCCUGGCUGAGGUGCAGAGUGAAAUCGAGCGAAUCUUCGAGCUGGCCCGGACCCUUCAGUUGGUCGCUCUGGAUGCUGACACCAUCAAUCACCCAGCCCAGCUGUCCAAGACCUCGCUGGCCCCCAUCAUUGUUUACAUCAAGAUCACCUCUCCCAAGGUACUUCAAAGGCUCAUCAAGUCCCGAGGAAAGUCUCAGUCCAAACACCUCAAUGUCCAAAUAGCGGCCUCGGAAAAGCUGGCACAGUGCCCCCCUGAAAUGUUUGACAUCAUCCUGGAUGAGAACCAAUUGGAGGAUGCCUGCGAGCAUCUGGCGGAGUACUUGGAAGCCUAUUGGAAGGCCACACACCCGCCCAGCAGCACGCCACCCAAUCCGCUGCUGAACCGCACCAUGGCUACCGCAGCCCUGGCUGCCAGCCCUGCCCCUGUCUCCAACCUCCAGGGACCCUACCUUGCUUCCGGGGACCAGCCACUGGAACGGGCCACCGGGGAGCACGCCAGCAUGCACGAGUACCCAGGGGAGCUGGGCCAGCCCCCAGGCCUUUACCCCAGCAGCCACCCACCAGGCCGGGCAGGCACGCUACGGGCACUGUCCCGCCAAGACACUUUUGAUGCCGACACCCCCGGCAGCCGAAACUCUGCCUACACGGAGCUGGGAGACUCAUGUGUGGACAUGGAGACUGACCCCUCAGAGGGGCCAGGGCUUGGAGACCCUGCAGGGGGCGGCACGCCCCCAGCCCGACAGGGAUCCUGGGAGGACGAGGAAGAAGACUAUGAGGAAGAGCUGACCGACAACCGGAACCGGGGCCGGAAUAAGGCCCGCUACUGCGCUGAGGGUGGGGGUCCAGUUUUGGGGCGCAACAAGAAUGAGCUGGAGGGCUGGGGACGAGGCGUCUACAUUCGCUGAGAGGCAGGGGCCACACGGCGGGAGGAAGGGCUCUGAGCCCAGGGGAGGGGAGGGAGCGAGGGGCUCACACCUGACAUGUAUUCGCCUCCAGGGGGCGCUGUCUCCCUCCUUUCAGAUGCCUUUGCUCAAAGCUUGGGGUUUCUUUGGUGUUACCAUCCCAGCUCCCGGGAGGCCCUUAAGCCCCAGCUGUCGGUUUUUACCUGCCUGUUGUGGAUGGAUGGGGGAUACCCACCUUUCUGAAGUGUCCCCUUUCUCCCAUCUUAAGGGGCUCUCCUCCCUCACCCUCCUAGAGAAAAGGUGCACUUCCUUAACUCUUUCUACUCGGGGCCCUAAGUGACGGUCCUAAGUGGGAUGGCUCUCCUUCUCCCAAGCUGCAGUACUGGGGAAGGGCUGGGCGCUUUUCCUGGAAAGGGAGGCCACAGAUUCUUUCCCAUGGGGGCUCUCUUCCCCAGACCCCAGAUCCAAGGUCCCUCACCCUGCCUGCCCCUUCCUCCCAGCUUCCUGGCAGCAUCGUCUGGUCGGUGAAAGCCAUAGCAUGGACACCCCAUGGGGAGCUUGUCUUGGGGAGGGUUCUGGGUGGAAGCUGGCAGGCAUACAGCACCCUCUACCCUCCGUGGCCAUGGCAACGUCCAGGGCCCAGAACCCUGAGGAGUGAGCGGCCGAGACGCUGCUCCCCACCCCCCACCUCCAUGCCUCAGCCUUUGCCUACCCCAGGAAUGAGCUUGGCCUCCAACAUCCCUUGCCUGCUGCCAUUAGUAGAGGGGGCCCCUCUGCAUCUGAGCCCCCCAUCCCUGUGCCACCUGGGUGUGGAGCCCAUGGAACACUCUGGUCCGCCUCAUUUUAAACCAAAAAACUGCUCCUUCACCCUCACCCUGAGGCCCCAGGGGAGAGGACCCGUGGGAUGGUGCCCAGGGGUUGCCUUGGGACCUCGGAUCUCCUCUGGGGGGCUUGGCUGCUGCUGUUGCUGCUCUGUAUUUGCCUCUCGUGAUUCUGUUUGUUACCCAUGUUCACUUCCCCCAGGAGAGGCCUUGGUACCCCCUCUCCCCUGGGGCAUCCCUUUGCCUUGGCAUCCCUGUAGCCCAGCAACCCUGCCCCUCCCCAGCAUCCCAGCUGGGCCAGAGAGAGCCGAGUGUGCCAACAAGGACUGGGGCCUGCCCGGCUGCCCGCCUCAGGGAUGGGCACCUCAUGCCUGUCUCGCCACCUCCUGUGCCAAUGUCCCACCCUCCACCUGGGGGUGGGGUGCAGCUUCCACUUACUGAUUAGAAGACACCACUGCCCUCCCUUCCCCCCUCCCUGUCUGGUGUCCUGUGCCCCCAUCUGUCUGUCUAUAUUUGUCUGUACUCCCCUAGGAGAAGUAUUUUGCCAUAUAUAAAACCACUGUCCUGUCCUUUGUGGCUGCCUCCCAAGCCUGCUUCUUUGUCCUCGCCACAUAGUCGUCAGCGUAGGCACCUGGGAGCUGCUGAUAUGCACGGGGAGUUGAAAGGGUGGGUGCCUGAAGAUGUUGUGCCCUGAGUCAUUGACUCAAAAGAAAAGAUGAUCCUUUGAUUUUGGCCCUCUGAUGUAUUGUGCCCAAGCCAGGAGCUGCUUGGGCAGUCCCAGCUCCACACUGGCCCUGAGCCCCUUCACUUACCUGUCUCUCCACAAGUAGAGCCAAAGGCAAUGGGAAGCUCAAUGUUGCUCAGUGGGUGAGAUCCAGACCCACUGGUGCAAUGUCUUAAAUACACAUGACUGUUUUUCUGC